AUCCGGCCUCGCACUUCCGGUGGGGAGAUUCCGGCCUGGAGCUCCCAGGGCCGAGAUUGAGUUGACAAGAAGGUGCCAGCAAAAAAGACCAAUAAGGAGUCCAGAAAAGCAGAAGAAAAACCAGGAGAAUGUGGUAUCGUGGCACCCAAGAGAAGGUUUUUUCUAGGAGGAGGAAGUGAUCCAUUGUGUAAGGUCACUUUGGUGGCAGUUCAUGGAGAAUAGCUUGAGGUGACAAGACAGCAGACACGACGUGGGUCUCUGGGACUGCCUGUGCCGUUGUGGGCAGCCCCUCCAGAGCCCUGAGUCACGCAGCCUUCAGAGGCACCCAUGGCUACGAGAAGCACAGUCUCUGCCUGAGGCUCCAGAGCGGCCCUUUUUCCCCAGCAGCAGACCUUGGGACCUGUGAGCGCUGCAUCCAAUUAACCAUGGGAAGGGUCAGCACCAGCCACCAGCCCCUUAGGUGAGGACUCUGCCUGGGGCUCUGCUGAUGGUUCCGAAUCAUGGAGCUGCAGAGAGCUCCUCCAGCCUGGAGACGUUCUUGGUGAAAGCUGUGGUCUAACUCCACCGGCUCUUCCUGCACAUUGUAUUCAAGAGGGGUGCCUGCCCCCGCUGACUCAGGAGCUCCGGUGCUGCAGCCGCCACGAAUGGGGAGGUGGGCCCUCGAUGUGGCCUUUUUGUGGAAGGCGGUGUUGACCCUGGGGCUGGUGCUUCUCUACUACUGCUUCUCCAUCGGCAUCACCUUCUACAACAAGUGGCUGACAAAGAGCUUCCAUUUCCCCCUCUUCAUGACGAUGCUGCACCUGGCCGUGAUCUUCCUCUUCUCCGCCCUGUCCAGGGCGCUGGUUCAGUGCUCCAGCCACAGGGCCCGUGUGGUGCUGAGCUGGGCCGACUACCUCAGAAGAGUGGCUCCCACAGCUCUGGCGACGGCGCUUGACGUGGGCUUGUCCAACUGGAGCUUCCUGUAUGUCACCGUCUCGCUGUACACAAUGACCAAAUCCUCAGCUGUCCUCUUCAUCUUGAUCUUCUCUCUGAUCUUCAAGCUGGAGGAGCUGCGCGCGGCACUGGUCCUGGUGGUCCUCCUCAUCGCCGGGGGUCUCUUCAUGUUCACCUACAAGUCCACACAGUUCAACGUGGAGGGCUUCGCCUUGGUGCUGGGGGCCUCGUUCAUCGGUGGCAUUCGCUGGACCCUCACCCAGAUGCUCCUGCAGAAGGCUGAACUCGGCCUCCAGAAUCCCAUCGACACCAUGUUCCACCUGCAGCCACUCAUGUUCCUGGGGCUCUUCCCUCUCUUUGCUGUAUUUGAAGGUCUCCAUUUGUCCACAUCUGAGAAAAUCUUCCGUUUCCAGGACACAGGGCUGCUCCUGCGGGUACUUGGGAGCCUCUUCCUUGGCGGGAUUCUCGCCUUUGGUUUGGGCUUCUCUGAGUUCCUCCUGGUCUCCAGAACCUCCAGCCUCACUCUCUCCAUUGCCGGCAUUUUUAAGGAAGUCUGCACUUUGCUGUUGGCAGCUCAUCUGCUGGGCGAUCAGAUCAGCCUCCUGAACUGGCUGGGCUUCGCCCUCUGCCUCUCGGGAAUAUCCCUCCACGUUGCCCUCAAAGCCCUGCAUUCCAGAGGUGAUGGUGGCCCCAAGGCCUUGAAGGGGCUGGGCUCCAGCCCCGACCUGGAGCUGCUGCUCCGGAGCAGCCAGCGGGAGGAAGGUGACAAUGAGGAGGAGGAGUACUUUGUGGCCCAGGGGCAGCAGUGACCAGCCAGGGCAAAUGGCUUAGAAGCAGGCCACUCCCCAGCCUGCUGCCAGCACUCACUGUGCUCAAGCCGCCAGGGCUCAUCAUGGUAGCUGGGAGCUGUGGACGGGAGUCACCAGGUGGUGGGGCCAAGCCAGGGACUCAUGACUUUUGCCCCUCCCUUCAGAGCCUGGUCACACAAGGGGCGAGCACCAGGCCAGCCUGGGACUGGCCAGAGCUGGGCCCAAGCUGCGCUGGAAUCGCAGCAGGAGAGGGGAGUGGGCUGGUUCUUCCCACCACUUCCCAGGCUCUGACAGCCGAGACUCAUUUCCAAGGCACAGCAGCUUUCUAAAGGGACUGAGUUUGGACUGGGUUUUGGACCUCCAGGGGCUGGAGCUUCAUCACCUGGGCAGUGUCUUUUCUCAGAGAGCAGGUUUCUUUAUAGUUUGGAAAUAAAUGGUUCACGGUCCACUGGCCGCCUUGUGUUGCUGGAGACGUGGGGGCAGGGAGGGGACAGUGUGGGCCUGGCCUCUCCUUUCCUUUCCCUGCCUGGAGCCUUCUUCAAAUGUCUGGUCUUAAGCCAGGCCUCCUUCAUUUUCUCGCUCCUGUUAGAACACCAGUCCCCUCCCCAGUGGGGCCCCACUGCACCUGCUGGCAGGAAAUAAAUGAAUGUUUACUGAGUACUGCAUUCUGGAGACCUUACAUGUUUUCACAGCCUAGUUUGAAUACUGGCUUUGUCACUAGCUGUGUGACCCUAAGCAAAUGACCUAACCUGUCUGUGCCGUAGUUUUUUAAUCUGUGAAAUGGGGAUAAUGUCUAUCUCAGAGUCCUUUUGAAGAUUGAGUCAUUAUUAGUAACAGAUUAAAUGUUAUAUAAGCAUUUCUUUUAAUCCUUUUAACAACUAAGAGACUAAAGCCUGGAAAAGAUAAAGAGCUGCUUAAGUGGCCGGGCUGAGGUUCACAUCCAAGUCUGUGUACGUCUGUGUGUGCACGUGCUGCACGUGACAUCCACACAGCCUCCUGGAACUUCAUGGGCCCCUGGGGCUUGGGCUUUCCACUCCUCCUUGGCCAAGUCCCACGUCUUCUCUAGACUGCAGGCCUCUCUCAAAUGAGGAAGGGAGGGGGCAAGACCCCAGCUCUGAUGUGCUGUGGACUGAGUCUACUCCUGUAAACUGGUUCCCGGGCCAUGGGAGACCCCCCCGGCCCUUGGGGACAAAGCUUUCCAGGCGAAGUGCUCCUAGGCACUCACAGCAGGUGGCGCCAUUGCACCACACUGGCUCCCAGAGCCCAGCUGCCCUGCCACGGCUAUCCAGACACCGGCAGAAAAGGGGUGCUUGGAAGAGGACAGUGGGUAUCCAUGGGUGGGGACAAGGAUAGGGCUUGUUCUAAAAUUGUUUCCAUCAGGUUGGAGUCACUAAAGCUCGUUCGGUUAAGCCCAGGAGAACUUUAAUACUUUAAAAAUGGGUCUGCAAACUUCCUGUAAAGGGCCAGAUAGUAAAUAUUUGGGGUUUGGGGACCAUAUGGCGUCUGUUGCAGCUACUCUGCCAUCGUAGCACAAAAGCAGCCAUAGAUGACACAGACCCAGGGUGUGGCUGUCCCAGUGAAACCCCAUUUACAAAAGUAGGAUCCAGCUUGCUGGCUGAAGUUUACCAGCAGGAGAACCCUCAAGAAUUCUCGAGUCCAACUUCCACUUCUGCAGCAGGAGACUGAAGCCAGGAGGGGGCGGUGACUAGCCCGAGGCCCUCAGAGCCUCCGUGCUCAGGAGUCAGACCGAGAUCUGCCUCUAAUUCAGAUUCCCAGCACAGACUCAGCAGGCGGAGGUGGAGCACCAAGGGCGCUUGGAAGCGGCCUCUUAUCUGGCUCCUGCACCUCUGCCCCCCUUGGAUUCCGCAAGCUCAGAGGCCAAGAUUAAAGGAGGCUCGUGCUCCAGCUGGAUGAUGUGGGAAGAGCCAGCCAAGGAGGGGGGCCAGGGCCUCCUCCGUCUUAGAGGCUGCUUGGGAUGCAGGCUGCUUGGGCGGCAGGGGGAGUCUGCCAGAGCCCCGCUGGCUCAGGUGGAUGAGAGCUUCCUGUCUGCUCCCCCACUGCCCGCCUCCCAGCACAGGGAGCAAGCGUUGCUGUCUGGUGCAGUAAUUACAAGGUGCAGAGCGGGGGCCCUUACCUCGCACAUGUUGGGUUCAAUGACAGCCCUUCAUUUAGCAGCAAUUACCAGCUGAACCUAAAGGAGGGCUCCCUCUCCUCCCCCACCCAGCCCACCCAAUCGCCUGGCCUCCCAGGCCAGACAGCGUCCACCUCGGCAUUGAGCCCUAGAACCACCCAUGCUGUCUGCAGCCAUUGCAUCUCAGGGCUGCAGCAUCACCAUGGCAACGCGGUGCUUGCACAGGUUGAGGGGAAGCUGAGGAUGUGACUUGUCUCUCCAAGGCUGUGGUGUCUGUCCCCACACAGCCCCAGCUCCGAGGCUUCUGCAGAAGGGGCGGAGAGAGGACUGACCUGCAGGUUCGAGUUUCAAGUGCUUACCUGCCCACCACCUCUCCCAGGGGCCCACAGUGGAAGGAAGGUUAAUGGCUCCAAUAUGUGAGGACGUCCACAGUUGGUGUUGUGGUGGCGGUGAGAAUGGGCUGCAGUUUGCCUGUGGGAGGGACCUGAGCCAUCAGGCAGGGCCCGGCAUACCUUCAUCUUCACUCCGGUACCCUUUUCUGCCUUGAGGGCUCAAGGGAUUGUCUCCAUCUGUUUCUGCUUUAUCCUGCUGUGAAAAACCUGAAAAUCCCAGUGGCUUGAGAGUAGUUACAUGGCACCAAGAGAAUUCUCCUCAUGGUACUUGCUGCAGCUUCCUGCAUCACACACUAGUGAUGGACUGAGGGUGGGGACUCCCAGGCCAUCCAUUUAGGUCGACAGCAUUCAGUGAGUACUGGCUACAUGGCAGACACUGCCGGACUUGGGGACAGAGACAUUCAUUUUUGGAGUCAGCCUUCCUCCCAGCCCAGGAAAGUGAUGAGGCAGUGGGCUGGGGAAUGGGGAAGAAAGAACAGAAAAGACCGUUCACUGGGCACCAUCUAGGCCUUUGCCAUAGGUUAUUUAAUCUGUAACAGCCCGGUGCAGUAAGGACUGAUUGUAUUUCUUUCCUAGCUGUGGAAACUAAGUUCCAAGUGGUUAAGCAUAACGAUGGCUAAGGAUACAACCUGCAGACGCCGUAGAGUGAGAGACGUGUCUCUCUUUGCUGUGAUUAGCUGCGUGCUUUUGGACACGUUGCUGAUCUUCUCCGAGCCUGUUUCCUUGUCUCUACAGAAGGAAUAAUAAUACAUACACCUGAAGGAAGCUACUGUGAAGGUGAAAUAAAAUAAUGUAGGUAAAGCACACAGUGCUCGGCUCAUAGUCAUCACCACUCAGGAAAUGGAGCAGGAAGGACGUCACAUAACUCGCCCAGAUGAGAGGAGGAGCCAGCGUUGGAGCUCUGGCCUUCCAAGAUCCCCAUCUCUGCUGCAGUGUCUGGUACUGAGCAUGCACUUAACAGAUGCUUUUUUUUUUUUUUUUUUGACAUGGAGUUUUUGCUCUUAUUGCCCAGGCUGGAGUGCAAUGGCACGAUCUUGGCUCGCUGCAACCUCCACCUCCCGGGUUCAAGUGAUUCUCCUGUCUCAGCUUCCCAAGUAGCUGGGAUUACAGGCACCCACCACCAUGCCUGGCUAAUUUUUUGUAUGUUUAGUACAGGGAGCUCUAAAGCUGAGAUGCCUUUCAGAGUUGUCCCAAGUUGGGGUGAGAGGUUCAUGGCUUUACGCCACAGCAUUUUUUGUAUUUUUAGUAUUUUGUAUUUUUGUAUUUCAGUACAUGUUGGCCAGGCCGGUCUUGAACUCCUGACCUCAGGUAAUCCACCUGCCUUGACCUCCCAAAGUGCUGGGAUUACAGGUGUGAGCCAUCGCACCCGGCCCAGAUGCUUGUUUUUUGAAGGAAUUUCCACUAGCGGAAACUAAAGUGGGGAUUUUACAGGUUCUAACUUCCAAAUGACUUGCCCUGUAAGAAGGGGCUGCUCCCUCCCACCACCGCCCAUUCCUGCCAGCCUCCGGUCUCCCAGCCAUCCCAUGGAGUUUUCACCCUAACUGCACAGCCCUGACAUCAGCCACGUCCCUUCACCCCUGCUUUGUAGUAACCAAUUAGCUUAACGUCUGUUCCCAUGGUUAUUUAGUUUCGUUGGCAACUAACAUACUUCCCAGAAACAGGCCAGCAUCUCCCAGUCCCACCACCAUCCUGCUGGUGGGGCCGUCCUCUUCUGGAUGUCAGAUGAGAACUCUCCUGCUGGGGAACAACAGAAGGACAGAACAUAGAACCAGAGGAAAAUGCAUUCAAAUGCAUUCCAUCAGUGUUUCUGGACAGUCUACAAUGUGCCCUGGCCGGUGAUCGCUGCUGGAGAUAUCGAAGUCAUUAAAACAUGGUCUCUGUCCUCAA